GCCAUUUCUAGUCGUUUUCAAAGCGCCUCGCGCUGAUUCUCACGGGCCCGGCUGCCGGCCCCCGCUCUGCCCUGGUGAGUCUCGCGCCGGCCCGUGGGGGGAGGGGCCGGGAGCCCCGAUGCGACCCGACUCAGCCCGGGCUCCGUGCCUGGUCCCGUUUCGUUUGCGCUCCGAGGCCCCGGGGUGGGGGUGGGGACGGGCUGGGGGCGGCUUCGGUCUAGUCCGCCCGCGCGGCUGUGGGCCUAGCCCGGCCGAAACGCUUCUCGCCCUCGCUCUUCCUCCCCCCGCCCCUUUAGCCCGCGGUCCGGCCCGCUGGGCGCUCUCCGCGCGGCCUGCUGGGGCCGGCCGUGCUUUUCCCGCCUCCGCUCGCUGCUCCAUGCGGCCGGAUCCCGCGAAGGGCCUGAGGCGCCCGCGGCCCUGCCGCUUCUCCCCGCCGGAGCCGCUUCGCUCCCGCCGCGGCCGGCCUAGCCCGAGAGGGAUGUGCUGAUGAUCCGGACGGGCCUGAGGGGAUGGGGGUGGGGGGCGGAAGGCGGGGUGCAGAUCCCAGGGUUAUCUGAGCCGGGAGAAAAGUUUUGUGUGAGCAGAAACCGAAAGGCCGAUUUGUGUGGGAAGCCUCCCUCCCCUCCCACAUUCUGCAUGCCGCGGGCUGAGAUUUGAAGGAAAAAAUGACUACUAGAGGCCGUAGAACUUAGGCUCCAAGCGGCGCCUGAAAUGGAUAAUUCUGAGACUGUCAGAGGCGCACCAAAUUGGAAAGGCGAUCCUUUUUCUUACACGCAGCAUAAUAAAAUGGCUAAUCAGGUGAAUGGUAAUGCGGUACAGUUAAAAGAAGAGGAAGAACCAAUGGAUACUUCCAGUGUAACUCACACAGAACACUACAAGACACUGAUAGAGGCAGGCCUCCCACAGAAGGUGGCAGAAAGACUUGAUGAAAUAUUUCAGACAGGAUUGGUAGCUUAUGUCGAUCUUGAUGAAAGAGCAAUUGAUGCUCUCAGGGAAUUUAAUGAAGAAGGAGCUCUGUCUGUACUACAGCAGUUCAAGGAAAGUGACUUAUCACAUGUUCAGAACAAAAGUGCAUUUUUAUGUGGAGUUAUGAAGACCUACAGGCAGAGAGAGAAACAGGGGAGCAAGGUGCAAGAGUCCACAAAGGGACCUGAUGAAGCGAAGAUCAAGGCCUUGCUUGAGAGAACUGGUUAUACUCUGGAUGUAACCACAGGACAGAGGAAGUAUGGUGGUCCUCCACCAGACAGUGUGUACUCUGGCGUGCAACCUGGAAUUGGAACGGAGGUAUUUGUAGGCAAAAUACCAAGGGAUUUAUAUGAGGAUGAGUUGGUGCCCCUUUUUGAGAAGGCCGGACCCAUUUGGGAUCUACGUCUUAUGAUGGAUCCACUGUCCGGUCAGAAUAGAGGGUAUGCAUUUAUCACCUUCUGUGGAAAGGAAGCUGCACAGGAAGCCGUGAAACUGUGUGACAGCUAUGAAAUUCGCCCUGGUAAACACCUUGGAGUGUGCAUUUCUGUGGCAAACAACAGACUUUUUGUUGGAUCCAUUCCGAAGAAUAAGACUAAAGAAAACAUUUUGGAAGAAUUCAGUAAAGUCACAGGUUUAACAGAGGGUUUGGUGGACGUUAUUCUCUAUCAUCAACCCGAUGACAAAAAGAAGAAUCGGGGGUUCUGCUUCCUUGAAUAUGAGGAUCACAAGUCAGCAGCACAAGCCAGACGCCGGCUGAUGAGUGGAAAAGUAAAAGUGUGGGGAAAUGUAGUUACAGUUGAAUGGGCUGACCCUGUGGAAGAACCAGAUCCAGAAGUCAUGGCUAAGGUAAAAGUUUUGUUUGUGAGAAACUUGGCUACUACGGUGACAGAAGAAAUAUUGGAAAAGUCAUUUUCUGAAUUUGGAAAACUCGAAAGAGUAAAGAAGUUGAAAGAUUAUGCAUUUGUUCAUUUUGAAGACAGAGGAGCAGCUGUUAAGGCUAUGGAUGAAAUGAAUGGCAAAGAAAUAGAAGGGGAAGAAAUUGAAAUAGUCUUAGCCAAGCCACCAGACAAGAAAAGGAAAGAGCGCCAAGCUGCUAGACAGGCCUCCAGAAGCACUGCGUAUGAAGAUUAUUACUACCACCCUCCUCCUCGCAUGCCACCUCCAAUUAGAGGUCGGGGUCGUGGUGGGGGGAGAGGUGGAUAUGGCUACCCUCCAGAUUACUACGGCUAUGAAGAUUACUAUGAUGAUUACUAUGGUUAUGAUUAUCACGACUAUCGUGGAGGCUAUGAAGAUCCCUACUACGGCUAUGAUGAUGGCUAUGCAGUAAGAGGAAGAGGAGGAGGAAGGGGAGGGCGAGGUGCUCCACCACCACCAAGGGGGAGGGGAGCACCACCUCCAAGAGGUAGAGCUGGCUAUUCACAGAGGGGGGCACCUUUGGGACCACCAAGAGGCUCUAGGGGUGGCAGAGGGGGUCCUGCUCAACAGCAGAGAGGCCGUGGUUCCCGUGGAUCUCGGGGCAAUCGUGGGGGCAAUGUAGGAGGCAAGAGAAAGGCAGAUGGGUACAACCAGCCUGAUUCCAAGCGUCGUCAGACCAACAACCAACAGAACUGGGGUUCCCAACCCAUCGCUCAGCAGCCGCUUCAGCAAGGUGGUGACUAUUCUGGUAACUAUGGUUACAAUAAUGACAACCAGGAAUUUUAUCAGGAUACUUAUGGGCAACAGUGGAAGUAGACAAGUAAGGGCUUGAAAAUGAUACUGGCAAGAUACGAUUGGCUCUAGAUCUACAUUCUUCAAAAAAAAAAAUUGGCUUAACUGUUUCAUCUUUAAGUAGCAUUUUGCUGCCAUUUGUAUUGGGCUGAAGAAAUCACUAUUGUGUAUAUACUCAAGUCUUUUUAUUUUUCCUCUUUUCAUAAAUGCUCUUGGACAUUAUUGGGCUUGCAGAGUUCCCUUAUUCUGGGGAUUACAAUGCUUUUAUCGUUUCAGGCUUCAUUUUAGCUUCAAAACAAGCUGGGCACACUGUUAAAUCAUGAUUUUGCAGAACCUUUGGUUUUGGACAGUUUCAUUUUUUUGGAUUUGGGAUAGAUUACAUAGGAGUAUGGAGUAUGCUGUAAAUAAAAAUACAAGCUAGUGCUUUGUCUUAGUAGUUUUAAGAAAUUAAAGCAAACAAAUUUAAGUUUUCUUGUAUUGAAAAUAACCUAUGAUUGUAUGUUUUGCAUUCCUAGAAGUAGGUUAACUGUGUUUUUAAAUUGUUAUAACUUCACACCUUUUUGAAAUCUGCCCUACAAAAUUUGUUUGGCUUAAACGUCAAAAGCCGUGACAAUUUGUUCUUUGAUGUGAUUGUAUUUCCAAUUUCUUGUUCAUGUAAGAUUUCAAUAAAACUAAAAAAUCUAUUCAAAACAUUACCUAUUUCAAAUUCAAUUGUGUCCUAAAACAUUAUUUUAUUCGUAAUCCUUGCAAGGAAUAUUGUUUUCAAAGUAUAACUGCCUAUGUGAGUGAUCAAAUUCAUGCAAAAUUUCUUGUUUAUUCCAACAUGUGUUGUGGAUAUUAGACUGAGGAUUAGUCUAAAUUCAAGUAUUUAUUCCAAUUAGCACUUUCAUUGAUUGGUGUUCUCUCAUAGUCUCUUCUAAUUUUGAAAUUUUAUCUUUUAUUAAAAAAAAAAAAACAGGUUCAUAGACUUUUGAGCAUUCUUGCAGGCAUUGGAUAAUUUGCAUUAAAACAAAUAAAAUGUGGCUGGGAAAGCAGACUGCAAUUUAUUUUGACCCACAUUCUUUAUAAGGGAUAAUUUGUGACUGAAGACCUUAUUUGCUGGAUAAGUGAAUGUACAUACAGGGAAAAUUGUUAGUACUGUGGCGUCAAUUGCACUGCGGACUUUAGUUUUAGUGAAAAUGAUCGUGACUACCAUUUCAGUUACUGGUUUAGGAAUAUAAUUUCCUAUUACUAUGUAAAUUUGCUUUGAGAAACAUUCAUGCCUUGUAAGAGAGGCUUAAAAAUAUCCAGUAGUAAUACCUUUGACUUUCUGUUAACACUUCGUUUAUUUUUAUUUAUCUGCUAUCCCUGAUGCCCAAAUUUUUUGUUGGCCAAGACAUAACAUCUAUUUCCCUAUUUCCUUUAGAAAUUCUGAUUUAUUCUAAUGACUUUUUUGCUUGAGAAUGAGAGGAACAAAAGAAUCUAAGCUUUACGGUACAGAAAAGUGAAUCACUUUCAAAUUACUAUUAAGUUUUCCCCUCCAUCUUAUUCUUACGUGGUUCUCAAAUGUUUUUAUAAUGAUAAAAAUAUCAGAAGCCAUUGGGGAAUAAUUAAAAUGGAUACACCAUUAUUCUGUGUUUUGUUCCUGUUUGGUGUCUUUGUGAUAGGAAUAUUAGAUUUCAAAAUCAUAAGCCACUUAAUUCCGUGUAAUCUUGGCUAGAUCAUAUUGGGUUUCAUGGCUUCUUUUCAUUUCAAUUUAAGAUUACUAUUUACUGAUGAAAGUCAAUAUAUUUCAUUUCUUUUUCAAAGUACACUCAUUACACAGUAUAGUCAUUUAACAGACCUUAUUGAUAUUUUAGUUUUUUGGAAACUGAUAAAGGAAUUAUGGUCUGUUGUAUGAUAGUUUUGAGUUAACAUGGGUAUUUCUUUGGUAAGACAGAUCCAGUUGUUUUUCUUAUGCCCAUGUAUGCAAGUAAAGACACCAAACAUUCUUUAAAUGCUGCUUUUAAACUUUGAAAGUACAAUUUGAAGUUGUAACUAUACAUCUAAUUAGACUUAAGUAAAACCCUGAUUUUUUUCCUGGAAAGAACAAAAUCUACAAAUAAAAUUUGAGUUGUUUGUAUUUCUUAAUUAGGUGUUACAAGCUACAAAGUUGUCAUAAAGAAUGCUAAGAAUGGGGAUAGAAAUGAUUCUGAGAAAACAAACCCUCGCAAAAACAUAAGAUUAAAACUUGGGUUCCAUGUCAAAAUCCUUUCCUUUAAUUGCAAAUUAUAUUUUGAAUUUUAAAGUGGCCACCUCCUCCUCUGUCCUUUUCACUAAUUAAAAAUAUAUUUGCAGAGGUACCCUCUAAUAUUUGGUUUAUAGGUUUUGUGGCUAUUUUAAAUUGUAAAGCAUAAUCCUAUAAACAUUAAAACUCAAGAGCUUUUCUUCUUUCAUGUCUUGUAAAUUAACACUGUAGCAGCAUUCAGAGAAAAUAGAUUCAGAGCUCAACUUUUCACAUAAAUAAAUCUAACAGUGUAAUAUAUAAACCUGAAAAAUGUCAGUUGAGGGAGGUCUUUAUUCUAGAUUGGCAUUUUUUUUUUUUUAAAUUAGGUACAAAUUAUGAGUGUAAGGAAUUUGGUUUCCUGCUCUCCUGUCUUUCCAUCUUUUUUGUUCCCCAAGCUAAUUGAUUUGGCUUUAUUUAUGAGCCUGUUACAGUAAAGUGUGUGUUGGGAAAUAUAUUGAGGUAUAGAGCUAUUCUUUGUAGGUACCCUGGUGAGACCGAUACAAAUAUGCCCCUCCCCAUAAUGGAAUACUAAUUUUUAUUUGAUCACUCAUUUAUAGCAGUUGCUUAAAUGUAUGUAUUUAUAUGAAGGUAUUUUAAUUUUUAAGAGCAAAAAAGUUCUAAUAAGUUGCCAGAUUUCUAAUAAAUGCAGGUUUAUUUGGUGAAAAGAUAAGGAAAAUGAGUUAUGAUUCUGUAGUUUUUUUAAAAUGAGUUCAGCAUAAUUGUUUUUCAGGUUUUUUUAGUUACUGGGGUUAUUCUGCAUAAGAAAGCCCAAUGCUUUCUGAUAGUAGGAGAUAAUUUUUCUCUCUUUUGACUUUGAAAUCUGACUUAGGAGAUGAAUUCUUUUUAAAAAGGUCAGCAUGCAAAAAAAUAAAUUAUAUAUUUUAAAUUCUAAAAGAGAAGGGACAUAAAAUUUCACUCCUAGCAUAAAGCCAUAUAAUAUUAUUCUUGAAACUCAUUACAUCAUUUGCCUCCUGCCCAUUUGAAUAUAAUCAUACCUACGUUUUAUUAAUUGUGCAUUUGUAAAACCAAACCCUUCCAGUAAAUACUUGCUAUAAGGCUAUUGCUUGUCAAUUAUCAAGGCUUCUAAAUAUGUUAAAACUUGUCAUUUUGAUUUUUCAAAGAUAAUUUUAUUAUACUGAGCUACCAAUAUUCUUAAAGAAAACUAACCAAAGUUAAUAUUAGUGUAGUCCAUUAUUAUGUGGACAAUUAUUAUGUGGAAUCUCUUAAGUGAGCAACUAAGAAAAAGCCUUAUAGAAAGACUACACUGGAUUUAUAAGUGUGUUUAUGUUUCUCUAAGAAUGGGAGCUUCUGUUAACUUAGGGGUGGAGUUGUUCUGAGGAAACCAGUAGAUUGGAUGACUGACUGGAGAAUCCAGAAUAACAAAUCCAUUAGCCAGACAUGUUUACUUUUAUAUUAGAAGUUUGUUGAUUAGGUCUUAAUUUUCAAACGCAAACACCAAGCUUUAAAAAUAUUGCAUAUACAAUGUAUUGGUCAGCAAUUUAAUAAUAUUUAAUUUGAAGUUAAUUAUUGUUAAUCCUUCUAGAAAAGUUUUUUUUCUUUAAAUAAAAGUACAUAUAUAUACUUUUUUAUUUAGAGGUUACCAGAAGCUCUGGUUUUGUUUUGUUUUGUUUUGUUUUUUUGUUUUUUUAAUCAUUUUCAGAUGUUAUCCAGAAAUCUGCAAGUGUACUUUUCCUGUUUUAACUCCUUCCUUUUAUCACCUGACUAUCAGGGAAGCGAGGUUGAGGCUGCCCUGACCUGACAUGUCAUGAUGUCGACUUGCUAGGUGGGGUUCGCUGGGGACGAUAACCAGUGGAAUUGUUGGUAAGAACUUUUUUUUCCUAUUUUUUUUUUUAUCAGUAGUGGGGCAUUAAGUGUGGGAGAAUGCCCAUAUCCUAUAAGUGGGCAAUUAUGUCAGCCUUGUAGAAAAAUAGGACUUUAAUAUUAAAUUAUUUUGUUCUUAAUAGGAACAUAUAAUAACACUUCACUUACUUUUAAAUUGGUAGCAGAUCAGCAGGAAAGGCCUGCAAGUAUGAAGUAAUGAAAUACUCAGGGUAUAUUUUAAGUGAGCAAAAUAGACACCUUAUAAUCUUAAAAAGUCUCUUGGAGAGACAAUAAAUUUGCUUUAACUGUCAUUUCAGUCUAGUAUUAUAUUUUCUAUAUUUUGUUGGAUAGAUUAACAUAUAAUGCAUCUUAAAGAGAUAUUUAUUGCACACUAAUUUUAGUGAAAACAAGAAGACAUUGAUAGAAUGGAGGGCUUAAACACCAAAGAUACUAUUUUUAAAAAUCUUCCAAAGUAAUCUUAACACUGUAAAAUGAAACUUUAAAAAGUUUUAGCAGUUUGACAAUAAUGGCCUCAAUUUAGAGAUAUGUUGAGACAAUGACUUUGGGUCAAGAGGAAAUUACAUAGCUGAAAUAUUAAGACCUUGAACAUAGCAGAAACAUAAACCUAUGAACAACUUGUGUUUUGUGUGAAAGCUAGGGUAGCUGAUAGGAUUAGCAGAUAUUGGUAGAAUUAAGAGUCAAUAUUUAAAUUAUUGCUAAAGAUUAAAAUCCCUCAUCUUAUAGUUUGUAGGGGAUUCCAUGAUGGUAAGGUAUAGAUUGAAAUUAAAUUUAGUAACUAGGCAUUUCUGACCAUACCAUAUAAAAAAUAAUUGUAAUAUGGUAUAAACACUGAUUAAAAGUAAUUAUGGAUUUUCAUGCCUGAAGAACCUUCUCAGUAUUCUUACAGCACUGUAUCUUCUUUAUUGGUUGAGAAUAUCAGUCUAGAAAGACUUUCCUAGAUGUUAAAUGUGCUAGUCAGUGUCAUGAAUAUAAACCCUUACUUGUAAGUUUGCUAUAGACUAGUUGUACAACACUAGAAUGAAAUUAUGUAAUACUUUUAAGAAUUGUAGUGAUUGCAGGGUUGUGUUAAGGUAACAUUUUAUGCAUGUGUCAGUGACAGAAAGGAUCAGGGUAUAAAACUUAGCACUAAAUAGCAUGCUCCUUAGGAAGUUUUAAGGUAAGCAGUAGGAAUAUUCAUGUAAUUCUGAUGAGUUUAUGUAAGUUAAGGAAAAUGCAAUGCCAGUUUGUUGACUUUAAACACUAAAAACAAAAUACAUUUUGUGGAACCAACAAAGGAGACAUUCUGGGGAAAAACUUAAAUUGCUCAAAUUUAAAUAAGGGCUCUCACUUUAUAUAGUAGAUUUGUCAGGAUCCCAUGAACAUUGCUUUUCUUGAUUUCUCACAUAUGAGGGUUGGGCAAAAGGGACUUCUCUAGCCUCUUCGAUAAUGUAGGUAGACUUGUACUUAGUGAAUCCCAUUAUAAUGUUAGGUACUAUGUUCUAAGACUAUUUCUAUAAUUGGACUGAAGGCUCCUGCAAACAUAAAUUGCUGAUAUGGAUAUAGUAACAUAAGAAAUACCAAAAUAGGGACAUUUGCAAGACCUUUUCCAUUUAAUCAUCAGUUUAAUAAAAAUCAUGCUUUUGGUACAGUGUUCAUGUACCAUAACUGUAUUGGAAUAUUUGUACGAUGUUAAAUAUUUUUAAUAAAAUUUAACAUGUUCAAAA